GAUGACACAAGUCUCUUUGGAUUUGGUUAUAAUUUUGAGAAAAAGCGACAUCUGUGAAUUUUUUUCAUAAGGGUUUUUAAAUUUGAUUUUUUUCAAACAGUGUGGAACCGAGGAAAUACUUAAAAUCAUACUGCUUUUAAACAUUGAAUUUAUUGAUUUACAUAAAUAUUUGAUUCCUGGUUUAAGACAGACACUCUUUUUAGGCAAACAGGCCAAUAUCCCUGUGGUCAUGAAGCUUAUAUUUAAGUGAAAGGAACCAUAUACUAAGCACACCAAAUAAGUAUAUUGUGUAGUAUGUUAGAAAGUAUAAGUGCUAUGGGGAAAAGAUAAACCAAGAAAGAGAUGGGGAGUGUUGAGGGGUUCAAUCUUAUGGGAUGGUCAUGGAAGGCUGAGACCUUUGAGCCAUCUUCUAAAGAAGGUAAGGGAGUAAGCCAUGCAGAUAUUUGAGAGAAGACUUUGCAGAAAGAAGGAAAAGCAAAUGCAGAGUCCCCGAGGUGGGAGCACAUGUCAUAUGUUUGAGGAGUGGGAAGGAGUAAGAGAGGUGAGUAAGGUGUGAGGUCUGAGACAAAGGGUGGGAGUGAGCCCGUGCUAGAUGGUGAAGGGUCUUGUUACCCAUGUAAGGAUUUGGGGUUUUCUUCUGAAGCAUGAGGUUACUGGAGGGUUUUGAGCAGAGGAGUGCCAUCAUCUAAAUUCUGUUUUAAAAGAAUCACUCUGCCAUGUGCAAAACAGACUGUGGGCGAGCAGGCAAAGGCAGAAGCAGGGAGAACCUUUUGAAAGCUGUUGCCAUCAUUGAGAAAUGGUCGGGGCAGGCCCAGUAUAGUUGUGGUGGAAGUGCUUUGAGAAGUGAUUGGAAUCUGGACCUGUAGCAUUUUGUUUAGGUGUAAGAGAAAGAAUAGUUUAAGGUGAUUCCAAGGUUUUUGGCCUGAACUACCAGAAUAACAACAACAAUGAUGAUAAUGAACUGUUGUGAAGUGUUCAGAAUGCCUGGCUCAUAGGAAGUGCUAUUUAUUCCUAGGGUAACCCUAAGAGGAAGGUACUAUUAGUAUUUCUGUUUUACAGCUGAGUGGACUAAGGUACAAAGAGGUUAAGAAGUUUCUCCAGAGCCACACAAUUACUUAGUGGUGGAGUCAGGAUUCAAAUCCAGAGCACUCUAGUCCCAGAGUCUGUGCUCUUACCCACUACUUGCACUAGAGGAUAGAGUUUGCUUCAGCUGGACAGGGUGAUUAUGGAAAAAGAAGGUUUCAGGGCAGGUAAGGAGUUUAGCUUUCAACAUUGUAAGUUUGAAAUGCCUAUGAGAAGUCAAAGUAGAGAUGGAUGUAUGGGCAGGCAGCUGGAUGUCUGAAUCUGGAGUUCUUGUGAGAGGUCUAGGCUAUAGCUAGUAUUUUGGAGUCACUGACACAUAGAUAUGAUUUAUGUGUCAGUGACUUUAAAGCCAUGAGAUCAAGAAUAAAUAUAUUUGAGUCACAAAUCAAUACUUUCUAACAGAUGAAUUCAUGUCACUUAAUACUGAAAUUACAGAAAAGUAAAUUUCAUAGGUAAUACAAAUAUACCUUUAAAAUCAGAAUGUCUUAAUAGAACUUUUCAUGCAAACAAUAGGCAGGAUACUUUCAAGAUACAAAUGAAGUAUAAAUUGCAUAGAAAGUCACCUUUACUUCAGUUUGGAUUAAGGUUUAUAGUCUUAGAAUCUUGAGAAUAAGUGACUUGCAAGCAUGUCUAACUUUUAUUCAUAUCUGACAAAAUAUUAAUGGCUAUCUCAGGGCCGAACAUCUUGGUAACAUCUUUGCUAAGAUCGUCUAUCAUUUAUUAUGGAGAAUUUCAGAUUUAUGUAAAAGCAGACAGAAGAACAUCAUGAGGUACUCUUUAUCUGUUUCCUGCCCCUAGCUACCGUCACCACAUGACUAAACUCCCAUUUGGUUCUUGGCUUUAAUUUUCGUUUUGAAGCAAAUUCAAAACUCUGCAUCAUUUCAUUUGUAAAUAUCACAAGAUGUGUUGAAAAAAUAGGAUAAUUCUUUUCCCUCUACAACAUAAUGACAAUAUCAUUAUCACAUAUAAAAAAUUAAAAAUAGCUUUUUAAUAUCAAUUAUCCAGUGUUCAAAUUACCAAUAGUCUCAAAUAUUGUGUUUUUUAAAUAAAUUAUUUUUUAAUCAGGAUCCAAAUAAGUCCACAUAUGGUGAUUGGUUUAUAUCUUUAAAGUCUCGAGGCUGUCUCCCUGUCUCUGUGAGUUCUUUCUCACUCUUUCUUUCCCUCUCCCUUCCUUUCUCCUUCCCCUCUUCCCUCUCCCUCCCUCCUUCUUCCUGCCUUUUCUGUUUCCCUGUUUCCCUUCUCUUUUUCUUCUUGCCAUUUUUUUAAGUGAAGAAACCAGUGUUUUGUCCUGUAGCAUUUUCCAUGAUCUAGAUUUUGUUGUUUGUCUGCCAUGGUGUAGUACAACUUGUUGCUUUAUCCUCUGUAUUUCCUGUAAGUUGGUAGUUGGAUCUAGAGGUUUGGUUAAAUUCACAUUCAAUUUUGUUGUUUUGGCAAUUACUUCAUGAGUGGUACUGUUGUCUUUCAUCACAGUGACAGAAUGUCUGCUUGUCUCUCUCUUUUCGUGAUAUCAGCAGUUAUUCAUGCUCAAUAACUAGGUGCUUGAUUCAUAGGGAUUAUAGUAGGGUUGCAUUUGAAUUCUGUCAUUCUUUCUUUGUUUCUUAGCUAGAAUACCUAUAAAGAAAAACUUCUCUUCUCCUGGUUAGUUACUGAGUGGUAUGGUUCAUAUAAGAAAAGUAGGAUAAGAUGCUGAAGUCUUUUCCGUUAUUUCCAGGUUUAAAAAAAAAAAUGCCAAGAAUUCCUUAGCAUCCUUCAUUGGUAAUUGAUUAGUGGCUCAGGUUUGUUUGUUUUACAUACCAUGGAUUUAGAUGAGUGCUUCUGGACAUUUUAGUCAUUAUAAUUGCACAGUCUUUUCUCUGACUAUUAGGAGCUUCUUCAAGUUGUUCUUAAGUCCUUUUGACAUGAUCCUAGUAGUCUUUGAUAGUUACUUUGCUAUUUGGUACGACAAGCUGUCCAGGCUCAUUUUGUGUAUUACUUCCCCAAGUAGGUAUCAGUCAUUUGUCCAGGGCAAUCUAAUCUCUUUUAGUGUGAAAUGAUAUUUGAAGGCCACAAUUAGGGUACUAGUAAUUUUUUGAUGUAUAUAUCUUUCAAGAUUUUUUUUCUAGGCACUGUGUGUGUGUGUGUGUGUGUGUGUGUGUGUGUGUGUGUGUGUGUGUGUGUGGUUUCUAUAUAUUUUAAAAAUAUGUAUAUAUUUGAGGGUGUUUUAAAAAUAAUAAAUAGACUCAUAAUGUACUUUUAAACUUGUUUUUCUCUUUAAGAGGGUAUUUCAUAGAUAUCAUUUUAUACCUAUUCACAUAGAUACACCAAACUGUUUUUUAAUAGACAGUAUUUUUAGGGUAGUUUUAGGUUCACAGCAAAAUUAAACAGAAGGUACAGAGAUUUCCCAUAUAUUCCUUGCCUCCACACAUAGAUAGGCUGCCUAAUUAUCAACAUCUCCCACCAGAGUGGUACAUUUGUUACAGUGGAUGAACUUACACUAUAGGCGCCCAAAGUCCGUCAUUUAUAUUACAGUUCACUUUUGGUGUUGUACAUUCUAGUGGUUUGGACAAAUGUGUAAUCACAUGUAUCCACCAUUAUAGUAUCAUACAGAAUAUUUCUACUGCCCUAAAAAUUAUCUUUAUUGUGUAUCCGCUAUAUAUCCCUCCAUCUCCCCAACUCCUUGCAACCACUGCUCUUUUUACUGCCUUUAUAGUUUUACCUCUUCCAGAAUGUCCUGUAAUAUGGAAUAAUACAAUAUGUAGCCUUUUCAGCUUGGCUUCUUUCAUUUAGUAUUAUGCAUUUAACUUUCUUCCAUGUCUUUUCAUGACUUGAUAGUUCAUUUAUUUUUAGUACUAAAUAAUAUUUCAUUGUUUCGAUGUACCACAGUUUUAUCCAUUGAAGGACAUCUUGAUUGCUUCCAAAUUGUGGCAUUUAUGAAUAAAGCUACUAUAACCUUGUGCAGGUUUUUGUAUGGACAUCAGUUUUCAACUCCUUUGGAUCAAAUGCCAAGGAACAUAAUUCCUGAAUCAUAUGGAAUCUGUUGUUGUGAAUAACAUUAGUAGGUAUUGUAAUGUUUGACCCUGGUUUGCAUUCCCGGAAUUCCUGUAAUAAGUCAGCCUGGUUAAGGUUGCUGCUCCAAGAUAGCCAAAAUGUGGAAGCACUGAGAAUGCAGGCACUCUACUAUGUGUGUAGAGAGGGGGAUAUAGAGAAGGCUUCCACCAAGCUGGAAAACUUGGGAAAUACAUUGGAUGCCAUGGAACCACAGAAUGCUCAACUUUUCUAUAACAUUACACUCGCCUUCAGCAGAACUUGUGGACGUAGUCAACUUAUUCUUCAAAAAAUUCAAACGUUACUUGAGAGAGCUUUUAGUUUAAACCCUCAGCAAUCAGAAUUUGCUACAGAACUUGGAUACCAAAUGAUUUUACAAGGAAGAGUUAAAGAGGCACUGAAGUGGUAUAAGACCGCCAUGACACUUGAUGAGACUAGUGUGUCUGCCCUAGUUGGAUUUAUCCAAUGUCAGUUGAUAGAAGGGCAAUUACAGGAUGCAGAUCAGCAGCUAGAAUUUUUAAAUGAAAUCCAGCAAUCCAUUGGAAAAUCUGCGGAAUUAAUCUAUUUACAUGCAGUUCUUGCCAUGAAGAAAAAUAAACGACAAGAAGAAGUUAUUAAUUUGUUAAAUGAUGUCCUGGACACUCACUUUUCACAAUUAGAAGGUUUGCCUCUUGGCAUACAGUAUUUUGAAAAGCUAAAUCCUGAUUUCUUGUUAGAAAUUGUUAUGGAGUAUCUGAGCUUCUGUCCAAUGCAGCCUGCAAGUCCUGGGCAACCUCUUUGUCCACUUCUCAGGCGUUGCAUCUCAGUCCUGGAGACUGUAGUAAGAACUGUUCCAGGUCUUCUGCAAACAGUCUUCCUAAUAGCAAAAGUGAAAUAUUUGUCAGGUGAUAUUGAAGCAGCUUUCAAUAACCUUCAGCACUGCUUAGAACACAAUCCCUCUUAUGCUGAUGCUCAUCUGCUGCUAGCUCAGGUUUACUUGUCUCAAGAAAAAGUCAAAUUGUGUUCUCAGUCUCUUGAACUUUGUCUGAGCUAUGAUUUUAAGGUGAGAGACUAUCCUUUAUACCAUUUGAUAAAAGCUCAGUCACAAAAGAAAAUGGGAGAAAUAGCAGACGCAAUUAAAACACUGCAUAUGGCAAUGAGUUUACCAGGAAUGAAAAGAAUUGGAGCUUCCACAAAAUCAAAAGACAGAAAAACUGAAGUUGAUACAAGCCAUCGUUUAUCGAUCUUUCUUGAAUUGAUAGACGUUCACCGCUUAAAUGGAGAGCAGCAUGAGGCAACCAAAGUUUUACAAGAUGCCAUCCAUGAAUUUUCUGGAACAUCUGAAGAAGUGCGGGUUACCAUUGCUAAUGCAGACCUUGCUCUAGCCCAAGGAGAUAUUGAACGGGCUUUAAGCAUCCUUCAGAAUGUUACAGCCGAACAGCCUUAUUUUAUAGAGGCCAGAGAAAAAAUGGCAGAUAUUUAUCUGAAGCACAGAAAAGAUAAAAUGUUAUAUAUCACUUGUUUUAGAGAAAUUGCUGAAAGAAUGGCUAACCCUCGGUCUUUUCUUCUCCUUGGUGAUGCAUACAUGAAUAUUCUAGAGCCUGAAGAAGCCAUAGUAGCAUAUGAGCAAGCAUUAAAUCAGAACCCGAAAGAUGGAACAUUGGCAAGCAAAAUGGGCAAAGCACUUAUCAAAACUCAUAACUACUCAAUGGCAAUCACUUACUAUGAAGCUGCUCUGAAAACUGGACAAAAGAAUUAUCUUUGCUAUGACCUGGCUGAGCUCUUAUUAAAAUUGAAAUGGUAUGACAAAGCAGAAAAAGUUCUUCAGCAUGCUCUGGCUCAUGAACCUGUAAAUGAACUGUCAGCUCUCAUGGAGGAUGGACGUUGUCAAGUUCUUCUAGCAAAAGUUUAUAGUAAAAUGGAAAAACUUGGUGAUGCGAUCACUGCAUUACAACAGGCUCGAGAAUUACAAGCUCGGGUACUAAAACGUGUUCAGAUGGAACAGCCAGAUGCAGUUCCUGCACAGAAACAUUUAGCAGCUGAAAUUUGUGCAGAGAUUGCAAAACAUUCUGUUGCUCAGCGAGACUAUGAAAAAGCAAUUAAGUUUUAUAGAGAGGCUCUGGUUCACUGCGAAACAGAUAAUAAGAUUAUGUUGGAACUGGCACGAUUAUACCUGGCACAAGAUGACCCUGAUUCCUGCCUGCGGCAGUGUGCUCUACUGCUUCAGAGUGACCAGGAUAACGAAGCUGCUACCAUGAUGAUGGCUGAUCUCAUGUUCAGAAAACAAGACUAUGAACAAGCAGUGUUUCAUUUACAGCAGCUUUUAGAACGUAAGCCAGAUAAUUAUAUGACAUUAUCUCGUUUGAUUGAUCUCCUAAGAAGAUGUGGAAAACUCGAGGAUGUCCCAAGAUUUUUCUCAAUGGCUGAGAAACGUAACUCCAGAGCAAAAUUGGAACCAGGAUUUCAGUAUUGUAAAGGACUGUAUCUUUGGUACACUGGAGAACCAAAUGAUGCCCUUCGACAUUUUAAUAAAGCUCGGAAAGAUCGUGACUGGGGCCAAAAUGCCCUUUAUAAUAUGAUAGAGAUCUGUUUGAAUCCAGAUAAUGAAACUGUUGGAGGUGAAGUAUUUGAAAACCUGGAUGGAGACCUGGGUAAUUCAACUGAGAAGCAAGAAUCUGUGCAACUGGCAGUAAGAACAGCAGAAAAACUUCUUAAGGAACUAAAACCUCAGACUGUUCAGGGUCACGUACAGCUUCGCAUAAUGGAAAACUAUUGCUUAAUGGCUACCAAACAGAAAUCUAAUGUUGAACAAGCAUUAAAUACCUUCACUGAAAUAGCAGCAUCUGAGAAGGAGCAUAUCCCAGCGCUCUUGGGAAUGGCAACGGCUUAUAUGAUCUUGAAACAGACUCCACGAGCCAGAAACCAGCUGAAGCGUAUUGCGAAAAUGAAUUGGAAUGCUAUUGAUGCUGAAGAGUUUGAGAAGAGUUGGCUGCUACUUGCUGAUAUUUACAUUCAAUCAGCAAAAUAUGACAUGGCAGAAGACCUGUUAAAACGGUGCCUGCGUCAUAAUAGAUCUUGCUGCAAAGCUUAUGAAUAUAUGGGAUACAUUAUGGAAAAAGAGCAAGCAUAUACAGAUGCUGCCUUGAACUAUGAGAUGGCAUGGAAAUAUAGCAAUCGGACAAAUCCGGCAGUAGGAUACAAACUGGCAUUUAAUUACUUAAAAGCAAAAAGAUAUGUGGAUUCAAUUGACAUAUGUCACCAGGUUCUUGAAGCACAUCCAACUUAUCCAAAAAUCAGAAAGGAUAUACUUGAUAAGGCCCGUGCGUCUUUAAGACCUUGAAAAUAAUUUUAACUUAGGUGUUGGUUUAACAGGAAAUGAAAGAAAUCUAACUUUCAGUUCUUCCUGUUCAAAACAGGUUUGAGCUCAGUGCUUUGUUAUUAGAAGUAUACCCUUUUUUCUCCAGCAGAGGUUGCUGCUGUACAUCAAGAGAAGUACUAUGUGAAAUUGGUGUUUCCUAAUGGAGUUGAAUGAGAGCUGGUCUAUUUGACUCUGUUUUGAUUGGGUACAGAUUUGGUGACUCUGUGGUAAAGACUAUAAUUAUUUCUAUAAAGAAUAUUUUGUUAAAAUCUAGGUAAUUAAAUACCCUGUAUCUUUUCUAAGGAAUAUUAUUUCAGGAAAUAUAUUUAAAAUGCAUUGUUCUCUUUUAAAGUGUUUUUGUUAUAUUCUUUUAUUUAUUUAUUUAUUUUUAAAGACAGAGCCUUGAUCUGCCGCCCAGGCUGGAGUGCAGUGGCACGAUCUUGGCUCACUGCAACCUCCGCCUCCUGGGUUUACGCGAUUCUCCUGCUUCAGCCUCCCGAGUAGCUGGGACUAAAGGCAUGUGCCAUCACACCCGGCUAAUUUUUUGUAUUUUUAGUAGAGAUGGGAUUUCACCGUGUUAGCCAGGAGGGGCUUGAUCUCUUGACCUUGUGAUCCACCUGCCUCGGCCUCCCAAAGUGCUGGGAUUACAGGCAUGAGCCACCGCACCCAGCCUGUUUUUGUUGUAUUCUGUGUUGUUUCAAAAAUUGGAAUAAAUCUCCCUGUAAAUAACUCAUGAAAAAGACAAUAUAUAUAUUUUAAAUAUAUAUUUUAAUAAAGGUUUUAUAAAUAGAUGAUUUAUAUUCCUCUUGGAACUCAAAAGAUGUGGUAAGUUUUGCAAAUCAGGGUAAGCUCCCCCUGCAUUCUGUAAUGUUAAUGGGUGGUGGUAUAGUACAGAAAAUGUAACUUUCAUUGAAAAAUCUUUUUUAGAAAAGGGUAGAGUGUGUGUUUCCCUUUCCUUUCUUGAGCUCAUUCUUCCUGCUUUCAAGGCCAUUGUGGUCUUAAGAAAUAAUCAGGUCCUGAAACCUCAAUUUAAAUAGGUCCCUUAUUAGGGAUAUUUAACCUUAGCCUAGAAGACUUGGUCUGCAGGUAUAAUUUCAGACACUGUAACAUUUGAUGGUAAAGGGUGACCAAAUACUUUUGGUCAGCAGGGAGUCACAAAGCACACCAUGUGAAGGCAACGGUUUACCCAGCUCUGUUUAACAGCACCCUGGCAUAGAAGCUUUCACUCUCUUACACUAAAUUUAACCUAAUCUAAACUUAAUCCUUAGCAUUAUUUUUAAUUUCUCAUCUACAUCUUUUUCAAUUUUCCUUAAAAUUGUAGUAAACACAGUCCUCAAUUUUAUUUGCAUUUACAAUAAACAGUAUUUAUAAGUCA